CCUCGCGGCUGGAGAACCCAACCGACAGUGGGCGGCAGGACGCACCGCGGACCCCGGAGAGAGCGGACGAGCAGGGCGCCGGCGCCAUGGACCUGGUCAUCACGCAGGAGCUGGCCCGCGCCGAGAGCCAGCAAGAUGCUGCGUCCUUGAAGAAGGCCUACGAGUUGAUCAAAUCGGCCAACCUAGGGAAAUCGGAGUUUGACCCCUCAGAGAGCUUCAGCCCAGACCUGUUUGUUCUGUGUGCAGAGCAGGCCCUGAAGAUGAGGCAGCCAGAGGUGAGCGAGGACUGCAUCCAAAUGUACUUCAAGGUGAAGGCGCCCAUCACCCAGUUUCUGGGCCGAGCGCACCUGUGCAGGGCCCAGAUGUGUGCCCCGAAGUCGGCAGAAAACCUGGAGGAAUUUGAAAAUUGCGUGACUGAGUACAUGAAGGCCAUAAACUUUGCCAAAGGAGAACCGAGGUACUACUUUUUGGUGUACAAUGCAUCAGUCCUCUACUGGCAGAUGGUGAGGCCGUUCCUCAAGCCUGGAUAUCGUCACCAUCUGAUCCCCAGCCUUUCCCAAAUCAUAAACGUGCUGAGUCAGACUGAGGAGGAAGACAAGGAGUGGCGUGCUGAGCUGAUGCUGGAACUUCUGGAGUGUUAUCUGCAAGCCGGAAGAAAGGAGGAGGCUGCCAGGUUCUGCUCCACGGCAGCUCCGUUCAUUAAGUCUCACGUGCCACAGAAAUACCGGCAGAUAUUCUCUGUUAUGGUUCGUCAUGAAUUAAUGGACGAACUUCAGUUAAAGGAAGAAAAGAAAAAUUCCAUUAGCCUGUCAGUCACUUUCUAUAUUAAUAUGCUAAAGGCAAAAGCGGAGCAAAAUGAUUUACCAGGUGACAUCAGUGUCAUUCUGAGGAAGGCCUACAGACACUUAGGUCAUUACAACCACCAGCGCUUUCCCUCUAUCAGUGAAGAAAAAAUGCUUUUGCUUUUUGAAUUGGCGCGUUUUUCCUUGACCUUGAAAUGCAUGGAGAUCUCCUCUGCCUGCCUCUCAGACCUGAAGAAGAUGGAAAGCAAAGAUCCUGGGAAGCUUAUUGAAAUGGAAUGUCUGGAGUGUGAAUCGGAAGCUUUAAGACUUGAAAGUAAGAUGAAAGUGUACAACCGAGCGGCUGUUGAGGCCCAGCUGGAUAUCAUACAGAGGCUAGACGUCGCGCUGCAGCGAGCCGUGCGCCUGGGCGACCCCCGGGUCAUCCACGUGGUGUGCGCCACGCAGUGGAACACCUGCCUGCCCCUGCUGCAGCACAACCUGCGGCACCACCUGCGGAAGCCCCUGGCUGGCGUUGCGGACGUGCUGGAGAAGCUGGACAGCCUCAUGACGCUUCUCCGCUGUCAAGUGCACAUGGAGAUGGCGCAGAUCGAGGAGGACGAGGACCGGCUGGAGCCCGCCACGGAGCACCUCCGGAAAGCCGCGCGCCUGGACAGCCUGGGCCUCUACCGGGACAGGAUCCAGAUGGCCUCCACCCGGCUGCGUCUGUGCACCACGCUAUACCAGGCCCCUGAGCGCGCAGAGGACAAGGCCAUCAUGGCCGUUGAGCAGGCAAAAAAAGCUACACCAAAGGACAGCGUCAGGAAGAAGCGGGCCCUCCUGGUGAAUGCAGGCCUGGCCUUAGCCCCUGACGCGUUUCAGAUUGUGCUGGACAGUGAGAAUGAGGCCAAAGUCUCCACCGGGAAGAACAGGGGCCGGUUCACCUACCUCUGUGCGAAGGCGUGGCACCACACCGUCAGCGUGGACAAAGCUGCCGGGCACCUGCGGCGCCUGGGCAACGAAAACGACAAGGAGAGGAUACAGAUUUGGGCAGAGCUGGCCAAAGUGGCCCGGAAACAAGGCGUGUGGGACGUCUGUCGGACGGCGAGCCGCUUCUGCCUCCUGUAUGACAACGUCAAGGUGAAGAAGUUGAGGCUGCGGCGAGGGAAGAAGAAGCGAGGUAGGGACGGCUCGGUGCAGGACACCUGGAGCCAGCCUGAGGUCGUCCUGCAGAGGCAGGUGUGCCCCGACCUGCUGCGGAAGUUCGCGGAGGUGGGGUUCAUCCAUGCUGAGGCCACGGUUCAUUUGCUGCGGUCAGAAGGUGUAGAGCUGAAUGACCGGGCCAUCCCCCCCGAAGACCUGAGCCAGCACCCAGCUGGCUACGUGCCUGAGCCCCCGGAGGUGAAUGCUGAGUGGAUCACAUACAGAACCUGGAUCGAGAGUCUGUCCCGGUGUGCCAUGAAUAACUGGCUGCGCUCCGCAGAGAUCGGACAGGAGAUCCAGGAGGCGUGGAUUGUGCAGAACGCCGUGGUCUACGUCCUGAACCACAACCACCACCUGAUCCUGGCCGGGCGGCAGAAGGAGCUGGUGGACGCCCUGUACCACCUCCUGAGCAUCGUUAAGGCCACAGGCCACAGUGGGGACCCCGUGAUGCUGGUGACGCUCUGCAACACCUUGGCGCGAGGCCUGAUCAUCAGCUGGAUUCCAGUCCAGGCUGCCGAGAAGUCCAGGAAAUUCAUGCGACCAAACGCGUUUCACAGCCCACUGGACGCAGGAGCCACUUCCGAGAUCAAAACAGCGGUGGAGGUCUGCGAGUUUGCCCUGAACCUGACCAAUGGGAGUGCGCCCGAGGAGACGGUGCCCACCGGCACCCGGCAGCAGCUUAUCGCCACCUGGGUCAAGGCCAAGCAGCUGCUGCAGCAGCAGAUUGGGCCACGGCUGGGCACCGAGGAGCAGGGCACCAAUGAGGAUGUCAGCUCGGUGACCAGAGUCCUCGUUGCCUUGGAAAUGUACUCAUGCAACGGGCUGGGCCUCAUGGACUUCACUGUCCCCUCCCUGGCCCAGUUGGUGAAAAUGGCUUCCGAGUGCAACUGGUCGGACCCCCUGGUGGAGCUGCAGACCCUGACGCGGCUGACCCACUUCGCCCAUGCAGCGCGUGACCAUGAGACCACCAUGGCCUGUGCUCACAGGGCUCUGGAGAUGGGCAUCAAGUACCUGAAGAAAUUUGGGCCCGAGGAGUCCCGGCUGGUGGCAGAGAUGCUGUGCACAGCCACGGCCAUCCAGGGCAGGAGCAUCAUGGAAAACCUGAAGGGCCGGAAGCAGCUGCGACUGGUGGCAGCCAAGGCCUUCACGGAGAGCGCCAGGUUCGGAGGCAUCGCGGGCAGCAGCGCCCUGGUGAUGCUGGCCGCGCGGCAUUACUGGAACGCCUGGCUCCCACUGCUGUCCUCAGCCGUCUACAGGAAGAAGGCCAAGGGUGCCCUGAAGAGGCUCAUCGGCAUCAUCAACAAGACAGAGGCCAGAAAGCAGGAGAAAGGAAAGACGCUGCUUCUGCACCAGUGGCCCACGGCCGACUUCCAGGGUGGCGGGACGACCGAAGGAUAUUUUCUUCCAGGGGCUGAGGACGACCUGGCGCUCCGUGCUGCGCUCUACGGCCUGCUCUUCCACAGCCAUGCCGACCAGGACGACUGGGAGGGCGGCCUCAAGGUGCUGGACGAGGCUGUGCAGGUGCUGCCAAGGACGGCCCACCGCCUCUUGAUCUUCAAGCACAUGGUCAUCGUGAAGGCCAAGCUCGGGCAGAAUUUUUCGAUGGAAAUACAGAAAUUCAAGGCCGAGAGUGAGGACUACUUGGCGCGCAUGUGGCACCGCCUGGCCCUGAACUCGCCGAGCGUGUCUGGAGAGCUGGCCUGCUACAACAACGCCAUCCAGGCCUUGCAGAAGCCUGAGAUGGAGUGGCAGAAGGUGGAGUACCUCAUGGAGUUCGGCCAGUGGCUCCAUCACAGACACUUUCCUCUCGAGGACGUGGUCUUCCACCUCCGCUGGGCUGUCGAGAUCCUGCUGGCCAUGAAGCCGCCCGGCGAUGUCCCUGAGCCACAGCCCACGCCGGAUGGGGAGUACGUGGCUGUGGAGAUGCCCCCACGGAGCCCCGUGUCCGAGGCCGAGGAGGCGGUGUCCUUGGAGCAGCUGCGUAGCGUGCGGCAGCUGGAGGCGCUGGCCCGCGUGCACAUCCUGCUGGCCCUGGUGCUGUCGCCGGGCGCCGAGGGCUACGAGGACUGCUGCCUUGCAGCCUACGCCUUCUUCAGGCACAUCUGGCAGGUUUCUUUGAUGACAGCAGGAAAAUCAGUUCUGGAAAACAGACCCCUGGCAGCAACCAGCUCACAUCUGUUAUUGCCUAAAAAAGAGAAGGAGAAUGAGAGGAGUAAAGAGAAGGAGAAGGAGAGGAGUAAAGAGAAGGAGAAUGAGAGGAGUAAAGAGAAGGACAAGGAGAAGGGAAAGGAGGAGAAAGUCAAGGAGCCCAAGCAGUCUCAAAGCCCAGCUCCUAUCAAACAACUGGAAGACUUACCCAUGAGCAUAGAAGAGUGGGCUUCCUACUCCUGCCCCGAGGAAGUGCUGUCUGUACUGAAACAGGACAGAAGUGACUCUACUGUGAACCCCUCAAGUAUCCAGAAGCCGACAUACAGUUUGUAUUUCCUGGACCACCUGGUCAAGGCCCUGCAGAAGAUGUGCCUGCACGAACUCACGGUUCCCGUCCUGCAGUUGGGGGUGCUGAUUUCGGACUCCGUGGUGGGAAGCAAGGGCCUGUCGGAUCUCUACCACCUUCGCCUCGCCCACGCGUGCUCCGAGCUGAAGCUGAGAGAAGCAGCCGCGCGCCAUGAAGAGGCGGUCGGGCAGGUGUGCGUCAGCGAGCUGGAGCAGGCCAGCUGCAGAAAAGAGAUCGCGUUGAAAAAAGAGAAAAAUAAGGAGCCUUUAUUAGAAGAAAGCCUGCCAGCACUGAAUGAGCAGACACUUCCUGUCCAGCCUGGGGAGAUCAAACCACUGGACGCCAAGGACAAGAUUUUGAAGAUGAAUGGGGAGACCGGGAGGGACCUGGAUGGGACGUCCUUUCCCCACCUGUGGAUGCUGAAGGCAGAAGUUCUGCUGGAGAUGAACCUGUACCAGCCUGCACGGCUGCUCCUGUCGGAGGCUUACCUGGCUUUCCAGGAGCUGGAUGAGCCUUGUGCAGAGGCCCAGUGCCUGCUCCUCCUCGCACAGUUGGCCAACAAGGAGAAAAACUAUGGACAAGCCAAGAAAAUGAUCGCACAGGCCCAGCACCUGGGCGGAAGUGAGGAGUUCUGGUACAAUUCCACUCUGACCCUGGCAGAGGCGCUCUUGUCCAUGGAACACUCAGGAAGGGAAGCUACGGUGUGUCACAUAUUUCAGAAGCUCAUCAAUGCCUUCAAGAUCCUCAAGAAAGAAAGACCAAACCGAUUGCCUUUACUGGAAUUCAUGAUCACAGAUCUAGAAGCCAGGUGCCUGAGCCUGCGGGUCAGAGUUGCGCAGCACUCAGCGGUCACUGAACCCACAGAGUGCUCGUUGCUACUGAAAGAGAUGGAUGAUGGCCUGUUGGAAAUUGAGAGAAAGUUUAUCGACUGUGGCUGCAAAGAGAAUUGUGUUGACGUAAAACUAGAGCGUGCGAAGAUCAAGAGGUUACGUGCCCAGAACGAGAAAGAUGAAGAACAAAAAACUGCGUAUUACUUGGAAGCGUAUGGCCUGGCCCAGGGUGCCGUAGCUGAGGAAGAAGGGAGGCUUCACAGCAUCCAGGGCUUAUAUGGCCUGGCCCAGGGCGCCAUGGCUGAGGAAGAAGGGAGGCUUCACAGCGUCCAGGGCCUAUUGUCACUUCAAGACUUGCAGAACGUCAACACGCCCCUGAUGAGGAAGCUGGCGCGCCUCAAGCUCGGCCUCGUGGAAAUGGCUCUGGACAUGCUCCAGUUCAUCUGGGAGGAGGCCCACGGGCAGCAGAGUGAGCAGGGGUCCCUGGAGAAGCUGCUGGCGGACUAUCUGCAGAACACCAGUGACUACACUUCCGUCGGCCUGCAAUGGUUCACGCUGAAGCGGACUCUAGCACACGGGGCACUGGCACAGCUGGGGAGCCUGCAGCCGCUGAGCGUGGGCUGUGUGGAGAUCCGCGCCCGGCUCCUGGGCCUGGCCGGGAGGGCCCUGCACCUGCUGGCCAUGCAAGCUGACCCUGUGCACCCUACCUGCUACUGGGAGGCGGGCCCCUCGGUGGGCGCCAAGCUGAGCGGCCUCAAGUCUCUGGAGCUGGAGGUAGAGGAAGAGGGUGCCACAAAGUCCAGCAGGGACCCGCCGGCCUCCAGGGCAGCCCCGGAGGAGCACUGCAGGAGAGGCGAGGACCUGAAGAGGAGGAUGGUUCUGGCCCAGCAGUACCUGGCUCAGGCGUCAGAGGUGCUGCUGCAGUGCCUACAGGUGGCCCUUGGCAGUGGCCUCCUGGAUGUCGCAGCAGCCGCCAGCCUGGAGAUGGUGGAGUGUGUCGGCACCCUGGACCCUGCAACUACCUGCCAGUUCCUGGCUCUGUCUCAGAGCUGCUCGGCCUCAGAGACGAUGAGGGAUGUCCUGCUUGCAGCCACAGCCAACACCAGCAGCUCACAGCUGGCGGCCCUGCUGCAGCUACAGCACCAGCUCCGGUGCCAAGACAGGACCACCACCAGCCUGGGCGCCCGUGUGGAGCAGAGGCUGGCCGCCGUGUCCAAGGCUUGGCAAAAUCUCUGCGUCACUGAGCAGCAUUUUAACCUCUUGAAUGAGAUGCCUCCGACCUUUUGGAUCCUCUUUCUGCACCUCUCAGGGGACAGCAGGUCCCGUCUGUACGGCGCUGCCUACGAGAAACCCAAGUUCAUUACUGCAGCCAAAGGAAAGGUGCAGGCGGUGGGAGGCUCCUGCAAGGUGAUGCGUCUGGCCAUAAGUCCCACUGCCUUCUCCCACCUGCUGGCCUGUGCCCAGCAGUUCCGGAAGCAGACCCAGGCCCAGGUGUACAGUGAGGACAUGGCCCUGAACAUAGGCUCGGAACCAGAAGGCCUGCAGGUGGAAGAGAAGGAGCGCCCUGUGCAGAGGCUCAGUAGCGUCCUGGGGCCCCUGGAGGAGCUUCUGCAGCCGCUAUUCCCCCUGCUCAGCCUCUCCAAGGCCAGAGUGCAGACACCUGCGGUUGUUGCCGAUUCAGGGAAGUCGAAGGGCAAAGACAAGGAGAGGAAAACGUCCACAGGACAACACAGCACAGUCCAGCCUGAGGUUGCCGAUAAGAUAGUCCUGGUCGCAGACAGACAUCUCCUGGAGCUGCCACUGGAAGGUCUCUCUGUGUUCGAUGAAGGGACAAUUUCCUCUGUGUCACGAGAAUUUUCUCUUCAAAUGCUGUGGAAUCGCCUCCAUAAAGAAGAGACAGAAGGUGGCGUGAAAAAGGAGGGAAGAAGCAGAGACCCCAAAAAGAGAAGCCUAGCGAAGAAGGGCAGGAAGGGCAGCAUCCCCCGGACCAUCCCCCCUGACUGCAUCAUAGUCGACUCAGACAACUUCAAGUUCGUCGUGGACCCAUACGAGGAGGCCCAGGGCCCAGAAAUGCUAACUCCUGUCUCCAUCACCCAAGACAUUUUGGAAAGAUUCCAAGACACAUUCACGUCGCGAUGGGCGGGACAUCUGGGAAGCAAGCACUUUCCCAGCCAGGCCCAGUGGGAGCAGGCCCUGGGCAGCUGCAGCGGUUUCUUCUUCUAUGGAAUGGAGAGCUUCCUGUCCCAUAUAUUAGUGGAGAGAUUGGUCGCCAUGAACUUGCAAGAGUGCCAGGUGGCAGUCCUGCUGGACCUGGCGCGGUCCUACCAGAGCUUGAAGAGGCACAUGGAGAGCGUGGAGCACAGGAGGUGCCUGGCUGCCUGGAACGGCGCCUCACAGCUGUCCCUGGAGGAGCCCGUUGAGGCGGCCAUCCUGCUGAGCCUGGUGGGCGUCAAGAGCAUCCUGGCAAACCAGUGGCCGACGCUGCUGCAGGACAACGCGCUGCGGGCCAGCGUCUUAUGGGAAAAUCUGUUGGCCGUUGGGAAGCCAAUUGGAGAAACAGUGCGUCUCCUUCAGAAGAUGAGUGGCGACGAGGCGGUGAACCAAGACGAGGCUUCUCAGACCUUGAAGGACAAGCUGCUGCUGCUCCAAAGCUCCGAGCUCCUUCCCACCACGCUCAACUUGGUCCUGUAUGGGCUGCCGCACCAAGCCAUCGGGUAGUGCAGGCCUGGACCUGCCUCCCAUCAGCUGCUGGGGCCCCAGCACUUGCCUCUGCCCUUGGCUCUGCCCCUCUGCCAACCCAUCCCCACCUCCCGGCUCCCAUCCCCAGCUCCCAGCUCGCUCUCCCCUUCCUGGGCCUCUCCCCAGCCCUUGGUGCAGCCUCAGCCAGGGACCCUCCCCCAGCGACUUCCCGCAAGGCAGCCGCCUGGACCUCGAGCUCUGCCUGCCUGUGUGCGCCAUGGGGUCUGCGUCGGGGCUGGAGCUGCGUCUCUUCCCGGGGCCAGGACAAGGGCGGCCUCCCCUUGGCGGCGCUGGUGCUGAGUUGCUUAGACCAGAAGACUAUUCAGACCGUGAGCCUGUUUUUGAUUUGAGUGUUCCACUAAACAAACAACAAAAGCCA